AGUUCGGAGCACAAAGCCGAGCGCGCACGCUCCGCCGUCCCCGCGCCCCGAAGAGUCGGCCAGCCCCGAACUGCCGGAGUAGGGGUGGGAACCAAACUUUUUCCUGCCCCGGGACAGACACGUUUACCCAAGGUCCAGCCUAGCCCCUAGGCACCAUGUCGGACAGUGAUCUAGGUGAGGACGAAGGCCUCCUCUCCCUGGCGGGCAAAAGGAAGCGCAGGGGGAACCUGCCCAAGGAGUCGGUGAAGAUCCUCCGGGACUGGCUGUACUUGCACCGCUACAACGCCUACCCCUCAGAGCAGGAGAAGCUGAGCCUUUCUGGACAGACCAACCUGUCAGUGCUGCAAGAUGAAUUUUUAGAUGUGAUCUACUGGUUCCGACAGAUCAUUGCUGUGGUCCUGGGUGUCAUUUGGGGAGUUUUGCCAUUACGAGGGUUCUUGGGAAUAGCAGGAUUCUGCCUGAUCAAUGCAGGAGUCCUGUACCUCUACUUCAGCAAUUACCUACAGAUUGAUGAGGAAGAAUAUGGUGGCACGUGGGAGCUCACGAAGGAAGGGUUUAUGACCUCUUUUGCCUUGUUCAUGGUCAUUUGGAUCAUCUUUUACACUGCCAUCCAUUAUGACUGAUGGUGUACAGCUCCCAAGUGCUCCCUAUCCAGUCCAAAGGACCCUCUUGAUUACAGCACAGGAACUUGAUCGUUGGGGAACCCCAGCCCCUUGGAACUUGGAAGACCCGUGUUUCCUGGACCGCGAAUCAGUGUGUUGGGCAUCAGUGUUUUCUGCAAGGGUUGUGACCUGAAACUUUUUAAAAACCACCCACCUUUGGGGAAGCAUUUCUGAAUUUAUCCAUCACCAACCAUUUCUUCUUGGAUACCAUCAAGUAACAGCUAUUAUUUGCCAAGUGGAGCUGUCAUUUAAUUUGAUGCACCUCUGGAUUCAGAUGAAACAUUAAAUUGUCUUCCUCGAUUCUCCAUCGGGUGUAGAGUUUUUAAACUAUCAAUGGCAUUUCAAGUCUUCUGAAACAGCAUGGCUGUAUGUGCGUGGUCCAUAGCACAGUACAUGCAGCAUCUAAUAAGAGUUUCCAUUGUAGAAUGUUUUCACAUACUUGAAUAAAUCAAAUCUUUAAUUGAGAA